GUCUCUCGCUGCAGCUGGAGCUGCAGGUCUCGCCUUCACUGCCCUGUGUCCUCUGCUCGCAGAGGCCCAGCCUCUGUGGCCCUGUGACCUGCAGGUAUUGAGAGAUCCACAGCUAAGACGCCAGGUACCCCGGAAGCCUAGAAAUGGGCGACCUGAGGUCUGGAGUGUAUCCUCUCAAGGGAGCAAGUGGAUCCCUGGGGCAGAGAGGAAGCUUCUAGUGUACUCUUACUUUGAAAAGGAGACGUUGACAUUUAGGGAUGUGGCCAUAGAAUUCUCUCUGGAGGAGUGGGAAUGCCUGAACCCUGCUCAGCAGAAUUUAUAUAUGAAUGUGAUGUUAGAGAACUACAAAAACCUGGUCUUCUUGGCAGGUAUUGCUGUCUCUAAGCAAGACCCGAUCACCAGUCUAGAGCAAGAAAAAGAGCCCUGGAAUAUGAAGAUAUGUGAGAUGGUGGAUGAAUCCCCAGCUAUGUGUUCUUCUUUUACCAGAGACCUUUGGCCAGAGCAAGACAUAAAAGAUUCUUUUCAACAAGUGAUACUGAGAAGACAUGGCAAAUGUGAACAUGAGAAUUUACAGUUAAGAAAAGGCUCCGCAAAUGUGGUUGAGUGUAAGGUGUACAAAAAAGGUUAUAAUGAACUAAACCAGUGUUUGACAACUACCCAGAGCAAAAUAUUUCCAUGUGAUAAAUAUAUAAAAGUCUUUCAUAAAAUUUUCAAUUCAAAUAGACACAAGACAAGACAUACUGGAGAGAAACCUUUCAAAUGUAAAAAAUGUGAUGAAUCAUUUUGCAUGCUUUUACACCUACAUCAACAUAAAAGAAUUCAUAUUAGAGAGAAUUCUUACCAAUGUGAAGAAUGUGACAAAGUGUUUAAGCGGUUCUCAACCCUUACUAGACACAAGAGAGUUCAUACUGGAGAGAAACCCUUCAAAUGUGAAGAAUGUGGCAAAGCUUUUAAGCACUCCUCAACCCUUACUACACAUAAGAUGAUUCAUACUGGAGAGAAACCCUACAGAUGUGAAGAAUGUGGCAAAGCCUUCUACCAUUCUUCACACCUUACUACACAUAAGGUAAUUCAUACUGGAGAGAAGCCCUUCAAAUGUGAAGAAUGUGGUAAAGCUUUUAACCACCCUUCAGCCCUUACUACACAUAAGUUCAUUCAUGUUAAAGAAAAACCCUACAAAUGUGAAGAAUGUGACAAAGCUUUUAACCGAUUCUCAUACCUUACUAAACAUAAGAUAAUUCAUUCUGGAGAGAAAUCUUACAAAUGUGAACAAUGUGGCAAAGGCUUUAACUGGUCUUCAACCCUUACAAAACAUAAAAGAAUUCAUACUGGAGAGAAACCCUACAAAUGUGAAGAAUGUGGCAAAGCCUUUAAUGUGUCUUCACACCUUACUACACAUAAGAUGAUUCAUACUGGAGAGAAACCCUACAAAUGUGAAGAAUGUGGCAAAGCCUUUAACCACUCCUCAAAACUUACUAUACAUAAGAUAAUUCAUACUGGAGAGAAACCUUACAAAUGUGAAGAAUGUGGCAAAGCUUUUAACCAAUCCUCAAACCUUACCAAACAUAAGAUAAUUCAUACUGGAGAGAAACUCUACAAAUGUGAAGAAUGUGGCAAAGCUUUUAACCGAUCCUCAAACCUUACUACACAUAAGAGAAUUCACACUGGAGAGAAACCCUACAAAUGUGAAGAAUGUGGCAAAGCUUUCAACCGAUCCUCAAACCUUACUAAACAUAACAUAAUUCAUACUGGAGAGAAAUCUUACAAAUGUGAAGAAUGUGGUAAAGCCUUUAACCAAUCCUCAACUCUUACUAAACAUAGGAAAAUUCAGCAGGGCAUGGUGGCUCAUGCCUGUAAUCCCAACACUUUGAGAGGACUAGGUGAGCAGAUCGCGAGGUCAGGAGUUCAAGACCAGCCUGGCCAACAUGGUAAAACCCCAUCUCUACUAAAAAUACAAAAAUUUGCUGGGUGUGGUGGCAGGCGCCUGUAAUCCCAGCUACUUGGGAGGCAGAGGCAGGAGAAUCAUUUGAACCUGGGAGGCAGAGGUUGCAGUGAGCCAAGAUCGCGCCAUUCUACUCCAGCCUGGGCCACAAGGCAAGACUCUGUCUCAAAAAAAAAAAAAAAAAGAAAAGAAAAUUCAUACUGGAACGAAACCCUACAAUUGUGAAGAAUGUGCCAGUGCUUUCAACCAGUCCUCGAACCUUUUUAAGAAAAUAAUUUAUACUGGAGAGAAAUUCUACAAAUGUGAAGAAUAUGGCAAAGCCUUUAACCAGUCUUCAACUCUUACUAGGCAUUAAAAAUUCAUACUGUACAGAAACCCUACGAGGGUGAAAAACAUGGCAAAGCCUUUAACAAGCCCUCAAUUCUUAACAGACAUAACAUAAUUCAUACUGGAAAGAAACUCUGCAAACCAGAAAGAUCUGGCAAUGCUUUUGACAACACCUCAAACUUUUCUAACCAUAAAAGAAAUUAUACUGGUGAGAAAUCUUAGAAAUCUGAAGAAUGAGACAAAGCCUUUAAAUGGUUGUCACACUUGAUUGUAGGUAAGAUAAUUCAUACUGGAGAAAACACCUACAUGUGUGAACAAUGUGGCAAAACUUAACCAGUGCUCACACCUUAUUGCACAGGAAAGCAUUUGUACUUGAGAUAAAUUAUACAAAUAUAAAGACUGAAAAAGCCAUUAAUAUAUGUUCAUAUCUCAACACCAGAUAGUUCAUACUUAAUAAAAGCAUUAUAAGUACAAUUACUGUCAAAAGACCUUUCAGAAAAUACAAGCUUUUGACCAGGCGUGGUGGCUCAGGCCUAUAAUCCCAGCACUUUGGUAGGCCAAGGCAGGUGGAUCAUGAGGUCAGGAGUUUGAGACCAGCCUAUCCAAGAUGGUGAAACCCCAUCUCUACUAAAAAUACAACAAUUAGCCGGUUGCGGUGGUGGUGCCUGUAAUCCCAGCUACUCAAGAGGCUGAGGCAGGAGAAUCACUUGAACUUGGGGAGGGAGAGGUUGCAGUGAGCUGAGAUUGCACUCUAGCCUGGGCCACAGAGCAAGACUCCAUCUAAAAAGUAAAAAAAAAAGAAAAUAUGAACUUUACAGUGAAGAAUAUUUAUUUUGAAGAUGAAUGUUACAAAUAUAAAGUGGGUAGUAGUGCCUUUACUUGUAUCACAGAUCUUAUUGUAGACAUUUUUUGUAGAGGAAAAACUCUGAAGCACUUUCACACUUUGUUCAAUAUCAGGGAAUUUAUAUUGAAGAAAAAUCAUGCAAAUGUAGUAAAUUUGGAAAAACACUUUUUCAAAAACUACAGCUUAGAAAACAGAGUUCAUACUAGAAUAUAUUUUUGCAGAUGCAGUAAAAGUUAAAAAAAAUUUAAUCCAUAAGUAAGUCUGUGUAAAUAUCAGAAUUUAUGGUAGAAAUACAUAAGGCACUGACAACAUCAGAUAUACUAAAUCAGAGGGCUGAGUAUAGAAAAUUAAAGUUGGUAGAAAAAUUAUUUGUAUAUAACUUUAAGAGGAUCAGAAGGUUUUUUGCAGUUAUAAUUACAUUCAAAGUAUACUUUAUUUCUUGAAAAAUAUUACAGAUUUUUUGAAAAGUGAAUAAUGAUGUCAUUCAACUCUGAAAUUCCUGCCGUUUCUUCAUUCCUAUUGGAUUCACAUGUGAAAGCAUGGGAUCAAUUAUUGCUGUAUCAAAGAUAUGAAAGAUUCUUUCUUUGUUUUGUUCUGUUUUUUUGAGAUGGAGUUUUGCUCUUUCGUCCAGGCUGGAGCACAGUGGCAUGAUCUCGGCUCACUGCAACCUUCAAUUUCCAGUUUCAAGCGAUUCUCCUCCCUCAGCCUCCUGAGUAGCUGGGAUUACAGGCGCAUAUCACCACGCCCAGCUAAUUUUUAUGUUUCUAGUACAGACAGGAUUUCAUCAUGUUGGCCAGGCUGGUCUCAAACUCCUCACCUUGUGAUCCACCCACCUUGGCCUCCAAAGGUGCUGGGAUUACACAGGCAUGAGCCACUGCUCCUGGCAAGAGAUUCUUUUUUAUUAGGUGGGCAUUAUUUGUGAUCUUUUCUAUUGAAAAGUAAAAACAUUAGAAUGUAAGAUGCAUAAUGAAAAUGUAAGUGGAGAGGUUCUUUGGGGUUAACUUAUAAUAUUGAGUGGUGCAUGAGGUUGGUGUUCAGAGUAAUAUUCUGCAUUAUGAAAAAACAUUUAAUUUUAUUUAAAAUUUAGUUUAUCAUACUAAUUGUACUUUUAUAUAAGAUGCAGUACAUUUUUAAAAUUUUAGAUUGUGUGAAGUUAAUAGUUUAACAUUUUUAACAUGUUAAAUACUAUUGUGCAUUCAAUGAAGCAUUAUUAUACCACAAACUUUACCCUGUUCCACCUUACUGAAGGGUAUAGGUAAAAGAUGGUAACGAUAUACUAUUUAGUAACAUAAUGGAUUAACAUCUCUAGUAAUUUUUUUUGCCAGUGGCUUUAAACCGCAAAUAAGUUAAAGAAUAUUGUUUCUGUAGGUUAAAUUUUUAUUUUGUUUUUAAUCAUUUAAAUUUAAUUUUGGUGGGUACAUAAUAUGAGUAUAUAUUUAUGCACUUAUAUGGCAUAUUUUAGUACAGGAAUACAAUAUAUAAUAGUAGCAUCAGGGUUAAGUGAGGCAUCCUUCACCCAUAGCAUUUCUCCUUUGUUUUACAAACAAUCCAAACCUACACUUUUUAAAAAUUUUUUGUUGUUGUUGUUCUUGUUGUUGUUGAGACGGAGUCUCGCUCUGUCGCCCAGGCUGGAGUGUGCAAUCUCGGCUCACUGCAAGCUCCACUUCCCGGGUUCACGCCAUUUUCCUGCCUCAGCCUCCCAAGCAGCUAGGACUACAGGCGCCCACCACCAUGCCCGGCUAAUUUUUUGUAUUUUUAGUAGAGAUGGGGUUUCACCAUGUUAGCCAGGAUGGUCUCAAUCUCCUGACCUCGUGAUCUGGUCUCGAUCUCCUGACCUCAUGAUCUGCCUGCCUUGACCUCCCAAAGUGCUGGGAUUACAGGCAUGAGCCACCGUGCCCGGCCACUUUUUAUAAAUUUUAAAAUGUACAAUUGUUAUUUACUAUAGAGUUAUUUUUAUGGUCAUAAUACAAAUUAUAUAUGAGUAUAAAUAAAAUUCAUUUCUAAACUAUUAAUAUUUUUUCCAAAUUGUUAUAUAUUUUUCUUUGAACAUGUGGCCUGUCUGCCUGCAAACAUGCAGACUUUUUGAUUCACAUAGAGUUAAAUAUGUAUUAGUCUAAAGACAAACUUUAGGUGUAAGAAAAUUAUGGAAUAAGUGUGUGUGUGUGAGUAUGAGUUUGUACCUAUUUUCAGAAAAGAACAAUAUGGGAAUAAAAAUCAUUUUAAUAAGGUGGCUACUAUAAAACUAAAAACCUUAAAAAAUGCUGAAAGCAAAUGUAUACUUUGUGCUUUGUAUUGAAUUUAUUACUGUACAAUCCAUGACUUACAGUUCUGAACCUUUUCAUGCAAAUUCUCUGUAUAUACUUGCCUGGUACUCAUGCUAGACCCAUACUUUUUUUGUUUCUUACAUUUUUUUUGUUUUAUGGUUUAGGAAGUAUUCAUUAUAUGAGCUGGUCUGUGAUUAUAAGAAUUUUUAUGAAAUUUAGUGCACACAAAAUAAUUUUUAGAUGUAAUUCCAAAAGUAGUGUAUUAAGUUACAUUUUAUUUAGUGAGAGCACUCCAUUUUGUUCUUUUAAGGGGAGAACAAUAUAUAAGUUUUCUUUUCUUUAGUGAUUGUUCCUUUCACUUUUUAUAAUUGACAUAAGUAUAUUUAUUUAUUGAGUCAAUUUGUUCAGGUAAGUACUGGGGGGCUUCAUAAGUCAUGAGGAUGUUUUUAUAUAUAAAUGUAGCAAACAUACAUUACAGUUCUUACUGUGUAAUCGAUGCUCCAUAAUAAUUCACAAAUAUUCCUGCUGGAGUUAGUUUGUAAUUUCAAGUCAGAAAUGAAAGAUAUCAGUGGUGAAGAAAUAAGAUUGAUUCUUCAUAUGGAGUGGACAUUUUUUCCAGACUAUAAAACUGAAUCUUGCUGAAUUUAAAGAGAAAUUCUGGCCGAGGCAGAUGGAUCACCUGAGGUUAGGAGUUUCAGACCAGCCUGGUGAAACCCGGUCUCUACUAAUAAACUACAAAAAUUAGCUGAUUGUGGUGGCAUCCACCUGUAGCCCAGCUACUCAGGAGGCUGAGGCAGAAGAAUUGCUUGAACCCAGGAGGCGAAGAUUGUGGUGAGCCGAGAUUGUGCCAUUGCACUACAGCCUGGGUGACAGAAUGAGACUCAUAAAAAAAAAAAUAAAUUCUGCUUCUUUUAUUUUCUACUUCUCUUCAGAUUUGUUUCUCGUAUGUAUUUUCCAACUAUGUAUGCAUCACAGCCCUUCUUUUUCUGAGUUAUAGCUACAGUUUUCUGACUGUUCUCUUCACGCCAUUUCAUUUCGCCUGGUAUUUUGUAGAUUUUGAUGACAAAAUUCUAUUUUUAGUGCACUUAAAAAUGGAUUUUAACUGGUGAGUUCGCUUAUCAAUAUAACAUUCAGAUUAGUUAAUUAAGAUAAAAGCCAGGUGUGGUGGCUCACGCCUCUAAUCCCAGCACUUUGAGAGGCCGAGGCAAGUGGAUCACUUGAGCUCAGGAGUUCGAGACCAGCCUGACCAACAUGGUGAAACCCCGUGUCUACUACAAAUACAAAAUUAGCCACAUGUUGUGGCGCAUGCCUGUAAUCCCAGCUACUCGGGAGGCUGAUGCAGGAGAAUCGCUUGAACCCAGGAGGCAGAGGUUGCAGUGAGCCGAAAUUGCGCCAUUGCACUCCAGCCUGGACAAGAGCAAAACUCUGUCUCAAAAAAAAAAAAAAAAAAAGAUUAAAGGCGCACACUGUCCACAGGCAAGAGGAUUAAAUUAGCAUUGCAUUUCUUUGUUUUUAAAAGAAAAAUCUUAUUAGAUUCUUAUACAAAGUGUGGCAAAUAUAAAACUUGCUUGAAAAUAUGGAAAUUAAAUUUUUAAGAGAGUUAAUAGUAAACGAAUUUAAUUUUCUUUUUUUAUUUUUACUUUUUAUUUUUUAGAGACAGAGUCUUGCUCUGUCUCCCAGGCUAGAGUACAGUGGUGUGAUCUUGGCUCACUGCAAGCUCCGCCUUCCGGGUUCACGCCAUUCUCCCGCCUCAGCCUCCCGAGUAGCUGGGACUACAGGCGCCCGCUACCGCACCCGUCUAAUUUUUUUGUAUUUUUAGUAGAGACGGGAUUUCACCAUGUUAGCCAGGAUGGUCUCAAUCUCCUGACCUCGUGAUCCGCCCGCCUCGACCUCCCAAAGUGGUGGGAUUACAGGCAUGAGCCACAGUGCCCGGCCACGAAUUUAAUUUUCUAUGAUAUAAUUACAGCACAAUUUACAUUUCCGUGCAGAAUCUUUUAAGUGUGGUGGUAAAGAUUGCAAAAUAAUAAAAUGACCUCUGAAUUUAAAAUUUAGAAAAAUAUGUCUUUUCUAUAUUGAUUUUACAAUUUGGAGAAAUUUCUCUUAUUUUUUAUAUUUUUUCUUUUAGUGGGAGAAGUUUAGUCUACGGUUUUUAUUUUUAGUCACCAAGCUGUAGCCAACUCCUGGGUCAUUUUCUCUGAAAAACAUUUGGAGAUCAUGACAAGUUUUGGAUUAAAACAUUCUGUUAUUUUGCAUGCAAACUAGUUUACUGUGUUCACAGACUGGCCAGUCAUGGGACCAUAAGCAACACCUGCCCCUUUAGUGGCUUUCAUACCAUUACCACCAGUACCAGAAACUCCAGGUGGCCCAAGCUUAAAGUAAAAAUCCUAAAGUACAUUGGCUUCUCCCAUGCAAUGUGCUGGGUCCAAACCAUGCUGUUAAAUAUCAGAGUUCCUAUGGUUAUGACUGACAAAUGACAAUAAUAGCCCCAAAAUACAUAUUUUUGAUACUAUUUAGCCAAGAUUACCACAAAGAUACAGUAUUUGACACAUUCUUAUUCUAUAACAUUUUGAAAAUAUUUUCUCUUGACAGAUAAAAAUGUGUACUUUUUCUGUAGAACAUAAUAUUUUGAACAUGCUGUUAAAUAUCAGAGUUCCUAUGAUUAUGACUAAAAAAUUAAAUGACAAUAGUCCCCAAACUAUGUAUUUUCAUACUAUUUAGCCAAAGUAAUCACAAAGACACAGUAUUUGACACAUUGUUAUUCUUUUAUGUCUUAAAAAUAUUUUCUUUCAACUUGAGAAAAUGUGUGCUUUUUCUGUAGAACAUAUUUUGAAGUAUAUAUACAUUGUUAUUAUUUCUAGGUAAUUAAUACCUCACAUAGUUAACAUUUUUGUGGUGAGACCACGUCUUAUCAUUUUUCAAAAAUCCAAAUACAUUAUUAUGAACUAUAGUCACCAUGUUGUACAAUAAAUCUCUUGAACUUAUUUCUCCUAUUUGACUAUAAUUACUUAUUAUUUGACAGACUUUCCAAACCCCCAUUUCUUCUAAAUACCUUGGCAUCUGAUGGUCACCAUUUUACUCUAUACAUCAAUGGGAUUAAGAUUUUUGGAAUCCAUGUAUAGGUGAAAUCAUGAAAUAUUAAUCUUUCUGUGCCUGGCCUAUCCCAACUAAUAUAAUGUCCUCCAGCUUAAUCUAUGUAAUUUAAAAUAAUAUAAUUUUUUUCUUUUUUUUUUUUUUUUUUAAGGCCAGGUGUGGUGUCUUACACCUGUAAUCCCAGCACUGUGGGAAGCCAGGGCAGGUGGAUUGCUUGAGCCCAGGAGUUUGAGACCAGCCUGGUCAACAUGGAAAAUCCCCGUCUCUACAAAAAAAAAAAAAAAA